ACUUCCGGGCUCGGCAGCUAGACUAGCGGGGGCAGCCUCAGAGCGGGUGAGCUUGGGGACGCACGGAGAGGUGCAGCUGGCCUUAGCCAUUAGAGAGAGGUCCUGCUAAAGAUGGACUGCAAAUGCGCUUGAUGGAAGGAGAUGUCAAUUCCACUGAAGUCCUCAUUUCUGCUGAGCUACCUGUGCACCCUGCCUCCGGCUCUCCUGAGCAGAGAGAUCCUGAUGGCUGACUCAGAAGCACUCCCCUCCCUUGCUGGGGACCCAGUGGCUGUGGAAGCCUUGCUCCGGGCCGUGUUUGGGGUUGUUGUGGAUGAGGCCAUUCAGAAAGGAACCAGUGUCUCCCAGAAGGUCUGUGAGUGGAAGGAGCCUGAGGAGCUGAAGCAGCUGCUGGAUUUGGAGCUGCGGAGCCAGGGCGAGUCACAGAAGCAGAUCCUGGAGCGGUGUCGGGCUGUGAUUCGCUACAGUGUCAAGACUGGUCACCCUCGGUUCUUCAACCAGCUCUUCUCUGGGUUGGAUCCCCAUGCUCUGGCCGGGCGCAUUAUCACUGAGAGCCUCAACACCAGCCAGUACACAUAUGAAAUCGCCCCCGUGUUUGUGCUCAUGGAAGAGGAGGUGCUGAGGAAACUGCGGGCCCUGGUGGGCUGGAGCUCUGGGGACGGAAUCUUCUGCCCUGGUGGCUCCAUCUCCAACAUGUAUGCUGUAAAUCUGGCCCGCUAUCAGCGCUACCCGGAUUGCAAGCAGAGGGGCCUCCGCACACUGCCGCCCCUGGCCCUAUUCACAUCGAAGGAGGUGGGGAAGAGGCACAGGCCCAACCCUGGGCUCCUGAUUCUAAUCUCCAGCCAGCUAAGUAGAGACCUUCCAGGUCUUCUCCCUGCCCUCCCUACAUCCUCCAAGGCCAGCCUGCCCCCAGGCGGAUGUGCUUCCUUCCAAUCAAGGAGUGUCACUACUCCAUCCAGAAGGGAGCUGCGUUUCUGGGACUUGGCACCGACAGUGUCCGAGUGGUCAAGGCUGAUGAGAGAGGGAAAAUGGUCCCCGAGGAUCUGGAGAGGCAGAUUGGUAUGGCCGAGGCUGAGGUUGACUUUUCACUUUUUUGAAACUUUUAUUUUGGAUUCAGGUGCUGUGCCGUUCCUGGUCAGUGCCACCUCUGGCACCACUGUGCUAGGGGCCUUUGACCCCCUGGAGGCAAUUGCUGAUGUGUGCCAGCGUCAUGGGCUAUGGCUGCAUGUGGAUGCUGCCUGGGGUGGGAGCGUCCUGCUGUCACAGACACACAGGCAUCUCCUGGAUGGGAUCCAGAGGGCUGACUCUGUGGCCUGGAAUCCCCACAAGCUCCUCGCAGCAGGCCUGCAAUGCUCUGCACUUCUUCUCCAGGAUACCUCGAACCUGCUCAAGCGCUGCCAUGGGUCCCAGGCCAGCUACCUUUUCCAGCAGGACAAGUUCUACGAUGUGGCUCUGGACACGGGAGACAAGGUGGUGCAGUGUGGCCGCCGUGUGGACUGUCUGAAGCUGUGGCUCAUGUGGAAGGCACAGGGCGAUCAAGGGCUGGAGCGGCGCAUCGACCAGGCCUUUGUCCUUGCCCGGUACCUGGUGGAGGAAAUGAAGAAGCGGGAAGGGUUUGAGCUAGUCAUGGAGCCUGAGUUUGUCAAUGUGUGUUUCUGGUUCGUACCCCCCAGCCUGCGAGGGAAGCAGGAGAGUCCAGAUUACCACGAAAGGCUGUCAAAGGUGGCCCCCGUGCUCAAGGAGCGCAUGGUGAAGGAGGGCUCCAUGAUGAUUGGCUACCAGCCCCACGGGACCCGGGGCAACUUCUUCCGUGUGGUUGUGGCCAACUCUGCACUGACCUGUGCUGAUAUGGACUUCCUCCUCAACGAGCUGGAGCGGCUAGGCCAGGACCUGUGAGCCUUCUCUGUCUUGCUGCCGGCCUUGAUACCACCCCUCACCCGCAGAGUCACUGCAUUCCCUCCCAGCCUUUGAGGCCGGGUGCAGUGGCUCACGCCUGUAAUCCCAGCACUUUGGGAGGCCGAGGCGGGUGGAUCACUUGAGGUCAGGAGUUCGAGACCAGCCUGGCCAAUAAGGUGAAACCCUGUCUCUACUAAAAAUACAAAAAUUAGCCGAGCAUGGUGGCCUGUGCCUGUAAACCCAGCUACUCAGGAGGUUGGGGCAGAAUUGCUUGAACCCAGGGGGCAGAGGUUGCAGUGAGCCGAGAUUGCACCCCUGCACUCCAGGCUGGGCAACAGUACGAGACUCUGUUCCAAAAAAAAUAAAAAAGAACAGCCUUUUUAGGCCACAGUGACCUGCGCAAUGUUUAUAUGCUUUGACCUACUAACUUUCUCCUAACUAAAUAUUUGAUUUUAGGAGAGUGUUUAAAUAAAUUACAGUAUGUCUAUAUGAUGAAAUGUUAUUUUGCCAUUAAAAUUUUGUUUACAAAGAUAAUUUUUAUUGACAUAAAAAUAACUUUAAUGUAAUUUAUGUUGAAAAAGCUGAAUACAAGUCUUUAUAUAGAGUAAUAUUUGAGCUGUGUUCAAAAAUACAUAGGAAAAGACUGAUAAAAUGAAAUAUGGCAAAAUGUUAAUAGUUUUCCCUGGAAUAGGAUAAUAGGCAAUUUUAAAACAGACUCCUUUAAAAAAACAAACAAACAAAAAAAACAUAGACUUCUUUAUAUCUUUUGAGCUCCCUCCCUUUUAUUAUGUAAUGAAUAUGUGUUGCUUUUGUAAUAGGAAAAUAAUAAAGUUAAAAUUUCAACUGCA